GUCUGGCCCCGCAGGCUCGGUGAAUCGAACGUUGAGCAGGGCGGUGGGUGGUGCGGAGUGCCGAGCGGCCUCACCCCCAACCGUCGGCCCAGUCGGACGGUUCCGAGGCGUUGCCGGGAGCCGGGCGCGGCUCUGUGUGGACUCGGAGAAACGCGGGUACAUUUGGGGACACCGGGGACGAGAGCCCAGCCCGGACUUGGGGGAGUCCGUCAGUGCCGGACGCGGGUCCCUGGCUUGCGGACGGGCUGGGGCCGGGGGCGUCCCCGUCUUUCCGGAGCUGGGGGCGGGGUUCGGGCCCGGGCAGAUGCGGCGUUCGGGCGGCCGAGCCCCGAAGUAAGAACUCCGUGGCGCGUGCAGCCCUAGGGAGGAAGGGCGUGCUGCGGGUGCAGUCUCAGGGGCGUCUGCCUGAGCCCGCUUUUCUACAAGAUGUGGGGAUUUUUGAAGCGCCCUGUAGUGGUGACGGCUGACAUCAACUUGAGCCUUGUGGCCCUGACUGGGAUGGGGUUACUGAGCCGGCUGUGGCGACUCACCUACCCGCGGGCUGUGGUGUAAGCUAAAUGACUCCAUUCCCAGGGUGAAUCUAGAAUUGUACUUUGUGACAGGAGGCGCCCUUACUGAAUAGCAUAAAUGGGAGAGUGAAAUCCUGGCUUCUUGGUGAUAGGUGUUUUUGGCAGUGAGAGGAGAGACCAGUCUGUCCCCAGGACAGCCCCAGCAGAGUACACCUUUUAGGUCUUGCCUUCUGAGUCUGUAACAGGUGAAAUUUGGCCCAUUAAAGGGGUGCAGUAGAGGAAAAUCUGGUUGCCAGCCUUAAGUAACAGUUUUAAAGUCUGGACGGCAGAGGAUUAAUGGAUUUGGAAUUUUGACGAAGUAUAUUAUGGGCAGUACAUCUCUUUUUACAUGAAACAAAUCUUCUUCUUGGAUGACAGUGGGCCGCCAUUUGGCCACAUGGUGCUGGCCUUGGGAGGUUAUUUAGGAGGAUUCGAUGGCAAUUUUUUGUGGAACAGAAUUGGAGCAGAAUACAGUAGCAACGUGCCUGUGUGGUCCCUGCGCCUGCUGCCAGCACUCGCGGGGGCCUUGUCGGUCCCCAUGGCCUACCAGAUAGUGUUGGAGCUCCACUUUUCUCAUUGUGCCGCCAUGGGAGCUGCUCUGUUGAUGCUUAUCGAGAAUGCUCUCAUCACUCAGUCAAGGCUAAUGCUUUUGGAAUCAGUGUUAAUAUUUUUCAAUCUAUUGGCCGUGUUGUCCUACCUGAAGUUCUUCAACUGCCAAAAGCACAGCCCUUUUUCUCUGAGCUGGUGGUUCUGGCUAACACUGACAGGGGUCGCUUGUUCCUGUGCAGUGGGCAUCAAGUACAUGGGUGUGUUCACGUACGUGCUCGUGCUGGGUGUUGCAGCUGUCCAUGCCUGGCACCUGCUUGGAGACCAGACUUUGUCCAAUGUAGGUGCUGAUGUCCAGUGCUGCAUGAGGCCGGCCUGUAUGGGGCAGAUGCAGAUGUCACAGGGGGUCUGUGUGUUCUGUCACUUGCUCGCCCGAGCAGUGGCUUUGCUGGUCAUCCCGGUCGUCCUGUACUUACUGUUCUUCUACGUCCACUUGAUUCUAGUCUUCCGCUCUGGGCCCCACGACCAAAUCAUGUCCAGUGCCUUCCAGGCCAGCUUAGAGGGAGGACUAGCUCGGAUCACUCAGGGUCAGCCACUGGAGGUGGCCUUUGGGUCCCAGGUCACUCUGAGGAACGUCUUUGGGAAACCUGUGCCCUGCUGGCUUCAUUCCCACCAGGACACCUACCCCAUGAUAUAUGAGAACGGCCGAGGCAGCUCCCACCAGCAACAGGUGACCUGUUACCCCUUCAAAGAUGUCAAUAACUGGUGGAUUGUAAAGGAUCCCAGGAGGCACCAGCUGGUGGUGAGCAGCCCUCCGAGACCUGUGAGGCACGGGGACAUGGUGCAGCUGGUCCACGGCAUGACCACCCGCUCCCUGAACACGCAUGAUGUUGCAGCCCCCCUGAGCCCCCAUUCACAGGAGGUCUCCUGCUACAUUGACUAUAACAUCUCCAUGCCCGCCCAGAACCUCUGGAGACUGGAAAUUGUGAACAGAGGAUCUGACACAGACGUCUGGAAGACCAUCCUCUCAGAGGUCCGCUUUGUGCACGUGAACACUUCCGCUGUCUUAAAGCUGAGCGGGGCUCACCUCCCUGACUGGGGGUAUCGGCAACUGGAGAUCGUCGGGGAGAAGCUGUCCCGGGGCUACCACGGGAGCACGGUGUGGAACGUGGAGGAGCACCGAUACGGCGCGAGCCAGGAGCAGAGGGAGCGGGAACGGGAGCUGCACUCACCUGCGCAGGUGGACGUCAGCAGGAACCUCAGCUUCAUGGCGAGAUUCUCGGAGCUGCAGUGGAGGAUGCUGGCGCUGAGAAGUGAUGACUCGGAACACAAGUACAGCUCCAGCCCACUGGAGUGGGUCACCCUGGACACCAAUAUUGCCUACUGGCUGCACCCCAGGACCAGCGCUCAGAUCCACCUACUUGGAAACAUAGUGAUCUGGGUUUCGGGCAGCCUCGCUCUGGCCAUCUACGCCCUGCUGUCCUUGUGGUACCUGCUCCGACGGCGAAGAAAUGUCCAUGACCUCCCUCAGGAUGCCUGGCUGCGCUGGGUGCUGGCUGGGGCGCUGUGUGCCGGUGGCUGGGCAGUGAACUACCUCCCGUUCUUCCUGAUGGAGAAGACACUCUUCCUCUACCACUACCUGCCCGCACUCACCUUCCAAAUCCUUCUGCUCCCUGUGGUCCUGCAGCACAUCAGCGACCACCUGUGCAGGUCCCAGCUCCAGAGGAGCAUCUUCAGCGCCCUGGUGGUGGCCUGGUACUCCUCCGCGUGCCACGUGUCCAACACGCUGCGCCCACUCACCUACGGGGACAAGUCACUCUCGCCACAUGAACUCAAGGCCCUUCGCUGGAAAGACAGCUGGGACAUCUUGAUCCGAAAACACUAGAACAAGAGUGUGGCAAAGAACACCCGUGCUGGGGUCGGGAUGAGGUUGAAGGGUCUUGGUCAAUGUACGUAAUGAGCAGGGUGGGCCCCACGCUGGGAGGACACGGGCUGGGCUGAGCAGGGCCUCUAGUGGAACACAUGGGGGUCUCAUUGAAAAGCUCUCUGAUGAGCACCUCCUUUUGUGCAAAGUUAAUUUUUUCUCGACAAUAAAGAUAUUCCGUGUCUUUACCCCUGAACUAAGACACAGGGAGUAUUUCAGAGGCCAGCGUAGGAGUCAUUGACAACAAAAAGCCGAGAACCCAGGGCCAGCAGUGGAGCCUCAGCAGACCAGGGCCUGGUCCUUGCUAACUGCUGCAGGGUGGAGUUUGAUCUGGCAGACCCGAUCCUCCUUCAUGAACACCCAGCAACCUGAGCAAGUCCCGGCCCUGCCCUCAGCGAGCCCGGCAGGCGUCCUGGGACAGCUCAGUGUUGGAGGGCCACCUGAACCACGAGCCAGGGCUGGGGCUUGCAUGUCAUUGUCUAUGACAGCGUCAAGACUGGCCCUUGGCACCGUGCUGUGUGGAAACCCUCCCCUCUGAGACUCCACUGAGACGUGGCUGAGUGAAAUCUUCCUCGUCAGUGGUCAAGGUGUGUCAUCCAUACAGCUCCAUGCCUUUGUCUUUUUUAAAUGUAAUUAAAAAAGGAACCAACUGGC